GUGCGUCGUGGCAGGUGAGCGGUGAUGAAGAAAGGGCGGAAGCUCCCGCUUGAGGGUAGACGCCACGGCCUCCGCUCCCGCGCGUUGUUGUCCUGCCUUACCGCGCUUGGAAACUCUGACUUGCGAGCCCUGGUCAGAGAGGAGCCUGGAGGGGCCACCUAAGCUCUGCACAAGGAAUUCAUCCAACUCUGUAGACAAAAUAUAAGGAAAAAGAAUAUAGACAAGCAUGGAAAGUGAAGACACAAAGAAAACACAAGAAAUGAAGACUGACCUGAACUUAUUAUUGGAGUGUCUAAAGUAUCAAAUGGACAAUGCUUUUUCACAAAAGGAAGCUUUGGUCACUAUUCAUUCAAUUUGUCAACAAAACAGUAAUGCAAGUGUUUAUUUUCGGGAAAUUGGUGGUUUGAUGUUUGUAAAAAAUCUUGCAAAGUCAAGUGAACAUAGCAUGGUAAAAGAAGCAGCCUUAUAUACAUUAGGAGCUAUUGCAGAGAAAAAUGUUUACUGUCAGCAGACUUUGUGUACUUCAGAGUUGUUUGAAGACUUAACUUGGUUCUUAUCUAAUGAUUCAAACAUAAAUUUGAAAAGAAUGUCUGUUUAUGUUAUUUUGGUUCUGGUUUCAAAUAAUAGGACCGGACAAACACUUGUGAGAGAAACAGGUUGUAUUACAGUUCUGUCACGGUUAUUCAGGACAGUUAUUUCAAAACAUGAGUUGGAUUUGUCAGAUAAAAAUGUUUUCCAGAGUUAUCAGUUGUGGUCUUCAGUGUGUAGUACUCUGUGUGUCUGUGUCAACAAUCCUCAAAAUGAUGAGAAUCAAAUGUUUUGCUGUUCCCUUUUUCCACAUGCUAAUGAAUGGCUAAAAAAUUGCACGACACCUGAGAUAAUUCGCCCUAUUUGCUCAUUUAUUGGACUCACUCUUGCAAAUAACACAUAUGUUCAGAAAUACUUCGUAUCUGUGGGCGGACUGGAUGUAUUGUCUCAAGUUCUCAUGCAGCUGGAAUCUGAUUCACAUGAGACUCUUUCCAGUGCUAAACUUGCAGUGGUUGUGACGAAGACUGUGGAUGCAUGCAUUGCUGAUAAUCCUACUUUUGGGAUAGUACUCUCCAAGUACCACAUUGUUUCUAAACUUCUGGCAUUACUGCUUCAUGAAAGUCUGGAUUCAGGAGAAAAAUUUAGCAUCAUGCUUACUCUUGGUCAUUGCACAGAGGAUUGUGAGGAAAAUCAGUAUGACCUUUUUAAAAACAAUGGGCUUCCACUCAUGAUUCAAGCCUUAACUGAAUCGCAGAAUGAGGAACUGAACAAAGCUGCCACAUUUGUGCUUCACAACUGCAAAAAAAUUACUGAGAAAUUAUCUCUAAGUCUAGGAGAAUAUCCUUUUGAUGAAAAUGAAACACAGCAAUUAAAGGACAUAAGUGUGAAGGAGAAUAAUCUUGAAGAGCACUGGAGGAAAGCAAAGGAAAUUCUACACAGAAUAGAACAGCUUGAAAGAGAAGGAAAUGAGGAAGAAAUACAAAGAGAAAACUAUCAGGAUAAUAUUUCAUCUAUGAACAUAAGUAUUCAGAAUACAUGGAAACAUCUCCAUGCAGAUCGGAUUGGUCGAGGUAGCAAAGCAGAAGAUGAGGAUAAAAGCCAUUCUAGACAGUUACAGAGUUAUAAGUCCCAUGGAGUCAUGUCUAAAGCAUGUACAAAUGAUGACCAAAUGAAGACACCGUUAAAGAGCGCAAAUCCAGUCCAUGCUUGUUACAGGGAGAGUGAGCAAAAUAAGACUUUAUAUAAAGCCAAGUCAAGCUGCAAUCAAAACUUACAUGAAGAAACUACUUUUGAAAAGAAUUUUGUUUCUCAAUCAAGUGACCAUGUUUUUAAACACCCAGUUCACAUUGCCAAAAAUAUAAAGCAGCAGUUACCAGUAACAGAUCCAUUUACAUUAUGUUCAGAUAUAAUAAAUAAAGAAGUAGUCAGUUUUCUAGCAACUCCCAGUUGUUCCGAAAUGUUGACGUAUAGGUGCUCAGGUUGCAUAGCAGUAGAAAAAUCCCUGAAUAGCCGAAACUUUAGCAAGCUCUUGCACUCUUGCCCAUACCAAUGUGAUCGUCACAAAGUCAUUGUGGAAGCUGAAGACAGAUAUAAAAGUGAACUAAGGAAAUCACUUAUCUGUAACAAAAAAAUUCUGCUGACCCCACGUAGAAGACAACGACUCAGUAAUGAAUCUACUACCCCUGGAGGAAUAAGUAAGACUUGCUUUAGCUAAAACCAAAUAAUCUGGCCUACUUUUUAGAAUUUAGAAAGGAACCUUGAGAAAGUAGUGAUUCUUACAUCUCUUUCACAAGCCGGCCAGGAAUAUUUGGUAUGUUGCCAUUUUUUCCCCCUUGAUAAACUUAACCUUUUUUUAGGAUACUCACCACCGUUCAUUUAAUUAUACUUUAUACUCAAAUGUGAGCCCAUUCUUCUGAGAAGGAACCACUGUCCUAAGCAUUUACAGAUUUCCCCAAGUCUCUAUUUCAGGAUGGAUUGGUGUUUUGAGAGGGCUUGAAAAAUAAAAGAGUCCUUAGAAUUAAGCCCUCUUGCCCAUUUUCCCUUGCUCUUCCCUAAUACCUAAUAUUACAAGGAGCACUAAAGAAGUCACAGAGCGGGGAGCUUGGGGUGUAGAGAGCUGCUUCCUUCUUCCAGGCUGCUCAGUACUCUGCUGUAGGAAUCUUUGAAGAUUUGGGCACAGAUAUUAAGUAUAAAAGUCAGGGAGAUGGCAGCCACAAUGGAAAAGUGGGGCUUUACAUGAUCAACUCCAGGGCUCAAUAUCCUGAAAGUUAUAGUAACCAAUCUAGUCCUGAUUAUUAUGGGUUCAAAUCAUUUAGCAAGGGAAGUUGAAACCUAUUUCUUGGAUAGCCACAGUUUUCCAGUACACCCAAAAUGAAAGAAUAAUUUCAUUGAUAAGCUUUGAGAUAGUUUUACCAAUAAAUUUUUUCUCUCAACAAGUAUUUAUUGACUACCUACUGUGUGUCAGAUACUAUUCUAAGCACUGGGGAUACAAUGGUGAAUAAAAUAGAUCAAAAUUGCUGCCCUCAUGGAGCUUACAUUCUAAAUAAUACUAUUAAGUAAUAAUCAGACAUUUACACUGAUAACCUUCUGCUGGGAAGAUUUUUUCAUCUGUUUUAAAAGGUCUGAACUGUGGCUCUUAGAAAAGGUAAACAAAUGGCUGUCUUGGCCUGCAAGGGCAAGGUUUUCUAAGGGUGACCCAGGACAACUGCACCCAGUACUACGAAAGUAAAUAACAGCCUCAACUGGAAAUACAGAAAACUUCUCCUCACCAGCAUCUACCCACAUUGAUAAGAUGAGAUAAUAAUGAAUGAAAAAGCUUAAAGAAAACUAUUUCCUAGUAAUCAUCACCAGAAAAUAUUUGUUUACAGAUACCAGCUGUAUAUUCUUUCUUUAUAGAAAGUAUCCCUUAAAAACCAAAUAGUUAAAAACUUCCUUCCUCAUUGUGCAGCCUAUAUUUUGAGUUUUGAUCUAGCUGACCAUGUGUUUUUAAAAGCAAAUUUCAAAAGACCCUUAUUCUUAAAAAUAUUAUCAAACCUAAUAUUUAACAAGUGUUGAUAUUCUUUUCUAUUCUAUCAAGUUAUGGAGCCCUUUGGGAAGACUGUAUCUCUAAGAUACGUAAGCUGUUUUUUAUUUUUAUUUAUUUAUAUAUUUUGAGACAGAGUCUUGCUCUGUCGCCCA